ACGUAUGGUGCCUCGCUCUGGGAUAGCUUUACGGCUUCUGGGAGCUGCUGCUUCGCUGUGAGAAGUAUCCGCGACGAGCUAUCCGGGAAAGGGCCGAAUGCGAUCAAACCUAAUCCGCGAGACUUGCUAAGGUUCUGUGCUACAAAUUGAUGUUUAGAUAAACUUCAGUGAAAUGACUCUUCAGGAAUUGGUGCAUAAGGCUGCCUCCUGUUAUAUGGACAGAGUAGCUGUAUGUUUUGAUGAAUGCAACAACCAGCUUCCAGUUUACUACACCUACAAGACUGUGGUUAAUGCUGCUUCUGAAUUAUCAAAUUUUCUGCUGUUACACUGUGACUUUCAAGGAAUUCGGGAAAUUGGUCUCUACUGCCAACCUGGGAUAGACUUACCCUCUUGGAUUUUAGGAAUUCUCCAAGUCCCGGCUGCUUAUGUACCUAUCGAGCCAGAUUCACCACCGUCAUUAUCAACUCAUUUUAUGAAAAAAUGUAAUCUAAAGUAUAUCCUUGUUGAAAAAAAACAAAUUAAUAAAUUUAAAUCUUUUCAUGAAACAUUAUUGAACUAUGAUACAUUUACAGUGGAACAUAAUGACCUAGUGCUCUUCAGACUUCACUGGAAAAAUACUGAGGUGAACUUGAUGCUAAAUGAUGGAAAAGAGAAAUAUGAAAAAGAAAAAAUAAAAAGCAUAAGUUCUGAGCAUGUCAAUGAAGAAAAAGCAGAAGAACACAUGGAUCUGAGGCUAAAGCAUUGCUUAGCCUAUGUUCUACAUACAUCAGGGACUACAGGGAUACCGAAGAUUGUCAGAGUGCCUCAUAAGUGUAUAGUACCAAAUAUCCAGCAUUUUCGGGUACUUUUUGACAUCACACAAGAAGAUGUUUUGUUUCUGGCUUCACCUCUGACCUUCGAUCCUUCUGUUGUGGAAAUAUUUCUUGCUCUAUCAAGUGGUGCCUCUCUGCUUAUUGUACCAACUUCCGUCAAGUUGCUCCCAUCAAAAUUAGCCAGCGUUCUCUUUUCCCAUCAUAGAGUGACUGUUUUGCAGGCAACACCAACAUUGCUUAGAAGAUUUGGAUCUCAGCUUAUCAAGUCAACUGUUUUGUCAGCCACUACUUCUCUUCGAGUAUUAGCCCUUGGUGGUGAAGCGUUUCCAUCAUUGACAGUUCUCAGAAGCUGGAGAGGAGAAGGCAAUAAAACACAAAUAUUUAAUGUUUAUGGUAUCACAGAGGUAUCAAGUUGGGCGACCAUUUAUAGGAUUCCAGAGAAGACUCUUAACUCUACUCUCAAAUGUGAAUUGCCUGUACAACUGGGAUUUCCACUUCUUGGAACAGUAGUUGAAGUCAGAGAUACUAAUGGCUUCACAAUUCAGGAAGGCAGUGGCCAAGUAUUUUUAGGUGGCAGAAACAGAGUGUGUUUUCUUGAUGAUGAAGUGACAGUACCACUUGGCACAAUGCGAGCUACAGGAGACUUUGUGACUGUGAAAGAUGGAGAGAUUUUUUUUUUGGGACGAAAAGACAGUCAGAUCAAACGUCAUGGCAAACGUCUUAACAUUGAACUUGUGCAACAGGUUGCUGAAGAGCUUCAGCAAGUGGAGUCUUGUGCAGUUACAUGGUAUAAUCAGGAAAAAUUAAUUCUCUUCAUGGUGUCUAAAGAUGCUUCAGUAAAAGAAUACAUCUUUAAAGAACUGCAGAAAUAUCUUCCAAGUCAUGCAGUCCCGGAUGAGCUUGUAUUGAUCGACUCUCUACCAUUUACAUCCCACGGCAAAAUUGAUGUUUCUGAGUUAAACAAGAUAUAUUUAAACUACAUAAACUUGAAGUCUGAGAAUAAGCUCAGUGGGAAAGAGGACCUUUGGGAAAAAUUACAGUAUUUGUGGAAGUCUACUCUGAAUCUCCCAGAAGAUCUUUUGAGGGUUCCUGAUGAGUCACUCUUCUUAAAUAGUGGUGGAGAUUCCUUAAAGUCCAUCCGGCUCCUCAGUGAGAUUGAAAAACUUGUUGGUACAUCAGUACCUGGGCUUCUGGAAAUUAUUCUCAGCAGUUCCAUUUUAGAGAUUUAUAAUCACAUCCUUCAAACAGUGGUUCCAGAUGAAGAUGUGACAUUCAGGAAGAGUUGUGCCACAAAAAGGAAACUCAGCGACAUUAAUCAAGAGGAAGCCAGUGGAACAUCUUUACAUCAGAAAGCCAUCAUGACUUUCACUUGCCACAAUGAGAUUAAUGCUUUUGUUGUACUGAGCAGAGGGAGUCAAAUUUUGUCUCUGAAUUCCACUAGGUUUUUAACAAAGUUAGGACAUUGCUCUUCAGCCUGUCCUUCUGACUCAGUUUCACAGACCAACAUUCAAAAUUUGAAAGGCUUAAAUUCUCCAGUUCUUAUUGGGAAGUCAAAAGAUCCAUCCUGUGUUGCAAAAGUUUCUGAAGAGGGGAAACCUGCGAUAGGGACUCAGAAAAUGGAGUUACAUGUGAGGUGGAGGUCAGACACAGGCAAAUGUGUAGAUGCUUCACCGCUGGUUGUAAUACCCACUUUUGAUAAGUCAUCUACAACUGUGUACAUUGGUUCCCAUUCUCAUAGAAUGAAGGCAGUUGACUUUUACUCUGGGAAGGUAAAAUGGGAACAGAUUUUGGGAGAUCGAAUUGAAUCCUCAGCAUGUGUAUCUAAGUGUGGAAACUUUAUUGUGGUGGAGACAGAGCUUCUGCGUGUUGUCCAGGCUGGUCUCAAACUCCCGGGCUCAAGCGAUCUGCCCACCUCAGCCUCCCAAAGUGCUGAGAUUACAGGCGUGAGCCACCAUGUCUGGCCUGGCUGUUAUAAUGGAUUAGUUUAUGUUCUGAAAAGUAAUAGUGGAGAAAAAUACUGGAUGUUUACUACUGAAGAUGCUGUCAAAAGCUCGGCAACCAUGGAUCCAACCACAGGACUCAUUUACAUUGGAUCUCAUGACCAGCACGCAUAUGCUUUAGAUAUUUAUAGAAAGAAGUGUGUUUGGAAGUCAAAAUGUGGAGGAACUGUCUUUUCCUCUCCGUGUUUGAACCUGAUUCCACAUCAUUUGUAUUUUGCUACAUUGGGAGGACUUUUACUGGCUGUAAAUCCUGCUACUGGGAACGUUAUUUGGAAACAUUCCUGUGGAAAACCACUCUUCUCUUCCCCACAAUGUUGCUCACAGUAUAUUUGUAUUGGCUGUGUAGAUGGGAAUUUACUCUGCUUUACUCACUUUGGAGAACAGGUUUGGCAGUUCUCUACCAGUGGACCAAUCUUUUCAUCCCCGUGUACCUCACCAUCAGAGCAAAAAAUAUUUUUUGGUUCCCAUGAUUGCUUUAUCUACUGUUGUAACAUGAAAGGUCACCUGCAGUGGAAAUUUGAAACUACUUCAAGGGUCUAUGCAACACCGUUUGCUUUCCAUAACUACAAUGGCAGCAAUGAAAUGUUGCUGGCAGCAGCAUCUACUGAUGGGAAAGUGUGGAUCUUGGAAUCUCAGAGUGGACAAUUGCAAAGUGUUUAUGAACUUCCUGGAGAAGUCUUCUCUUCUCCUGUGGUCCUGGAAUCAAUGCUCAUUAUUGGGUGUAGAGAUAAUUAUGUUUAUUGUCUGGAUUUAUUGGGUGGCAAUCAAAAAUAAUCAAAUACAGUCCUUAUUUGUAUAACAAAUGUGAGAUAUUUGAAAAUAUUUUACCAUUAUACAUCAUGUGGACUUAUUUUAUAUUAAAGAAGAUUAUAUUUUGGCUAAGAAA